CAAAAAUGUUUCGGAUUUUGGAUUUUUUCAGAUUUGGGGAUAUUUGUGUAUAUGUAUAAUAUCUUCAGGAUGAGACCCACAUCUAAACACGAUAUUGAUUUAUAUUUCAUAUCCACCUUAAUACGCAUAGCCUGAAGGUAAUUUUAUACAGUAUUUUACAUUAUUCUGCACAUGAAGCAAGUUUGUCUUAAGUACUUAUGUGAAAUUUUCCACUCAUGCUCGCAUCCUGUUGAACUCAAAAAGUUUCCAGUUUUCGAGUAUUUCAUAUCUUCAGAUUAGGGAUGCUCAACUUGUAUUAUUCUGUCUUCCGGCAUCUACUGCGACUAAUUAGAAGUUCAUCAAUCUAGUUAUUCCUUUGUAGAUUAUGGCUCUUUUCUCUCUGAUUGUUUUAAAGAUAAAAUAUUUGUCUUUGGUACUCUGCAGUUUCACUACAAUACAUCUAGGUGCAGAUUUCUUUUUAUUUUUCUCUUCAGAACUCUGUGUGUGUGUGUGUGUGUGUGUGUGUGUGUGUUUUCAGUAUAUUAUAAAGAAACAUUGUCAGUUUCUCAACCAUUAUCUCUUUGAAUUUUGCCUUUCCCUUAUUCUUUCAUAUCUUUCUACAAGUCCUCUAUUAGAUGCAGUAGUAUUUUCAUUCUGUUUCUCAUUUUCUCUUCCAUAUAUUCCAUUGCUUUAUAAGCUCUGCUGCUUUCUGGUUGCUAUUCUCUUAUCCAUCUUCCAGUUCACCUUUCUCUGUAGUCUCAAGUACCUUCUGCUGUUUAACCUAUUCAUUGAUUGUUACAUUUUAUGAUGAUAUAUUUUCUAGAAGUCUUAAUUGAUUCUUUUUCAAAUUUUGCCUUUUCACUUUAUAUCUUAUUGUUAUGAUUUCCUUUUAUCUCCACAGUCAUUUUAAAUAUUUUUAUUUUAUAGCUUCUUUCAGGUUCUGUUCUCUUACAUUCUUAGAUAUUAAUCAUCUAAUUAAUGUUCCUGAUCUUUACUCAUGGUGGAUUAUUUCUUUGUGCUUUUGAAUUUUAUUUAACAUGAGCUCAUUUUCAACAUGAUGUUAUUUGUUUUUCAUUUUUUAACUCUAGAAAUCCUUUGCUUCCUGGGUUAAAGAAAUAAGAUUCCAUAGCAGUUUUACUUUUGUUUCUGCCAGGAAUCCUAUGGUAUCACCAGCCUCAGACCAAUUUUUUUGUUAAUUUCUAUUUUAAGUUUCUUUUCUACACCUGUAGUGUAAAUUUGGAUUCCACACCUGUGCAUGGUGCGGGCUCGUGUCUUUAAUUUUGUAAGGGAGAUGUUUCCUUCCCACUCAUGGCUCUAGUGAAUUUCAGUUCUUGUGGCUUCUAUGUGGCAAUGGAUAGAGAUUUAGCUGCUUUUUUCUAGUAAGGAAGGACCUUCCAGAAUCUCUGCUUUAUGCAACUAUUUCAUUUAAAUAAAAUGUCUUUCUGAUGUGGUCCUAUAAUGUGUCUUCUUUCCACAUAGUAUUAAAACCCCAGCUCCAGUAUGUCUAGUUCUGAUAACUAUAUCUCUCUCCUUCCAAACUCUUCUCCCCCACAUAUCACCACAGUAUUUUAACUUAAACACUUAUUAUAGUGGCUUUUAAUUCUGUCUUUGUUUCUGGCACCAGGGAAUUUUUUUCUUGCAAGCUCUGCUGUUACAAAACAAAGUCAAUCAUUUUUUCAUUAUUUCUGGUUUUUCAUAACAGAAGAGGUUCUGAACUAGCUCAGUACACUAUCAUUCUGGAACUGAAGCCAAGUUUUUUUCUCCCAAAAGUAAGACUUAAAUUUUCCUAAAUGUGCUUUUGGUAUCUAUUGAGAUAAUAGUAUAAGUAGUCUCCAUUAACUAUUAAUAUAAUGGAAGUACAUUAAUAAGUUUAGUUUAAAGUGAGAUACCAGUAAUAAAUCCAGCUCUAUAGUUUGUAUACUCCGUUUCCUAAUCUUUUAUUCAAAAUUUUUGUGCCAGUUUUUUUAAAGUAAAUGCUCUUGGUAUAUAGGUAUUUUGUUUGCUUUAUUUGCAUGUUAGAUUUUUACAUCAGAAAAUGAUAGCCUUUUUUUUCUGAAUUUUUUUUUAUGUUAGCCUGUGUUAGUUUGUUCUUGCAUUGCUAUAAAGAAGUACCCAAGACUGGGUAAUUUAGAAAGAAUAAGGGUUUAAUUGGCUCCUAGUUCUGCAGGCUGUACAGGAAGUAUGUUGCCAAGCAUCGGCUCACCUUUUGGUGGGGCUUCAGGAAGCUUACAAUCAUGGCCGAAGGCACAGGGGAAGCCAGUGUGUCACAUGGCAAGAGCGGAAGCAAGGGAGGAGGAAGUUUUAAACAGCCUGAUCUCAUGACAACUCAAUCAUGAGAACAGUGCCAAGGCAGGGGGCACUAAACCAUUCAUAAGAAAUCCACCCUCAUGGUCCAGUCGCCUCCCACCAGGUCCCAUCUCCAACACUGGGGAUCAUAAUUCAACAUGAGAUUUAGAGAAGACAGCAUCCAAACUAUAUUAUUCCGCCCCUGCCUCUCAAAAUCUCAUGUUCUUCUCACAUUUCAAAAUAUAAUCAUUCCUUCCUAAUAGUCCUCCAAAAGUUUCAGCUCAUUUCAGCGUCACUCAAAAGUCCAAAGUAUCAUCUGAGUUAAGCCAAGUCCCCUUUACCUAUGAGUCUGUAAAAUCAAAACAAGUUAUUCACUUUCAAGAUACAAUGGGGGUACAGGCAUGGGGUAAACAUUCCCAUUCCAAAAGGGAGAAAUUGGCCAAAAGAAAGGGGCUACAGGCUUCAUACAGGUUUAAAACCCAGUAGGGCAGUCAUUAAAUCUUAAAGCUCCAAAAUAAUCUCCUUUGACUCCAUGUCCCGCAUCCAGGCCUUUGAGCAGCCCUGCCUGUGUCUGCAGGGUUCAGCCACGGCAGGUGUUCUCGUGGGUUGGAGUUGAGUGUCUGCAGCUUUUUCUAGCACAAGGUGUAAGCUGCUGGUGGACCUAACAUUCUAGGGUCUGGAGGACGGGGGUCCCUUUCCCCAGCCCCACUAGGCAGUGCCCCCAUGGAGACUCUGUGGGGCCUCCAACUCCACAUUUUCCCUCCCUACAGCCCUAGUAGAGGUUUUUUUGUGAGGGCUCUGCCCCUGCAGCAGGCUUCUGCCUGGCCACCCAGACUUUCUCAUACAUCCUCUGAAAUCUAGGUGGAGGCUGCCAAGCCUCCUUCACUCUUGCACUGUGCACACCUGUAGGCUUAACACCAUAGACACUGCCAAGGUUUAAGGUGGCAUACAUUCUCCAAAGCAGCAGCAGCCCGAGUUGUUCUUGGGGCCCUUUGAGCCAUAGCUGGAGCGGCCUGGAUUCAGGGAGCAGUGUCCUGAGCUGUGCAGGGCUGGGCCUGGCCACCUGAACCAUUAUUUCCUCCUGGUUUCUGAGCCUGUGAUGGGAGGGGCUGCUGCAAAGAUCUCUGAAAUGUCUUCGAGGCCUUUUUCCCAUUGUCUUGGCUGUUCGCACUUGGCUCCUUUUUAGUUGGGCCAAUCUCUAGCAAGUGGUGAGUCCACUUGCUUGAAUUCCUCUCCCGAAAAAGCCUUUUCUUUCUCUGCCACAUGGCCAGACUGCAUGUUUUCCAAACUUUUAUAGUUCUACUUCCCCUUUAAAUAUAACUUCCAACAUUAAGUCAUUUCUUUGCUCCAACAUCUGAGUAUAGGUUGUUAGAAACAUCCAGUCCACAUCAGAAAUUUCUUCUGUCAGAUGCCCUAAAUCAUCACUCUUAAGUUGAAACUUCCACAGAUCCCCAGGGCAUGAACACAAUACAGCCAAGCUCUUUGCUAAGGCAUAACAAGGCUGACUUUGCUCUGGUUCCUAUAAGUUCUUGAUUUCCAUCUUAGUUUUUAUCACCUUGGCCUUCCCUGUCCAUAUCACUAUCAAGAUUUUGAUUAUAACCAUUUAACCAGUCUCUAAGAAUUUUCAGAUAUUCCCUCAUCUUCCUGUCUUCCUGAGUCCUGCAAACUCUUCUAACCUCUGCCUGUUACCCAGUUCCCAAGUUGCUUCCACAUUUUCAAGUAUCUUUAUAGUAGUGCCCCAUUCCCAGUAUCAGUUUUCUAUGUUAGACCAUUCUUGCAUUGCUGUAAAGACAUACCCAAGAUUAGGUAAUUCAGAAUGAAAAGAGGUUUAAUCGGCUCAUGGUUCUGCAGGCUGUACAGGAAGCAUGGUGCUGGGCAUCUGCUUCGCUUCUGGCGGGACCUCAGGAAGCUUACAGCUAUGGCAGAAGGCAAAGGGGGAACCUGGAUAUCACAUAGAGCGGGUGCAAGAGACAGGAGGUGCCACACACUUUUGAACAGCCAUAUCUCACAAGAACUCACUAUCCUGAGGACAGCGCUAAGGGGAUGGCACUAAACCACUUAUGAGAAAUCCGUCUCCAUGAUUCAUUCACCAUCAGGCCCCACCUCCAACACUGGGGAUCACAGUUCAGAAUGAGAUUUAGAGGAGAUAAUGCCCUAACUAUAUUAUAACCUUUUAAAGUAAAUUGAAAACUGAAAUUUGUCUGGACUUUGGAACAAUUUAAAUUACACAAAAAUUAACCUUUUUUUGGAAAGUUUUAGAAAACUAUCCCAUCUGGCUUGGUGUACUGGGGAGGGGAAACUAGUCAAGAGCAGUUAACUUCAAUCUUUGACAGACUUUGCCAUAUUUUUAUAGUCAUUGUUUUGAGGUGUUGUUUUGUUUUUAAUAUCAAGGCAGCUUGUUUUCUAGAAAAUAAUUCAUCUAAUCUAAAUCUAUAACUUAAGUACAAUAGUAAUGUUUCUCCCUUGUCCCCUCCCUCCCAUUUCUCCCCAUUUUCCCUAGUGUUAGAAUUGCAAGAGCUUUGUUAUUUUAUCAGACUUGGUUGAAUACCAGCUUUGGUCACAAAUGAUUAAUAUUCUACAGUUUUUUAAAUUAAAAUUAUACUUUUCUUCCCUGAAUACCACUACAGGAAGGGACCUUGGAGAUUUAGUCCAUCCCUCAUUAUUGACUAAGUAUCUAGGCUAACAGUAUUUAUAGGGGGAAAAUGUAAUAUAAACAUUGAAUAUUGAUUACACAAAAAUUGUAAAGUAACUGGGCAGAGGAGUAUAGCAGUGGAGAAGUAUGGUGUAUAUAUAUAUAUGGGGUAGGCACUGAGUUCUAAAGCUAAAUCUUUAUUUUCUCAUAAAUGGCACUAAACCAUUUAUGAGAAAUUCGCCCCUAUGAUUCAUUCACCACCAGGCCUCACCUCCAACAAUAGGUAGGAAUGUGGAGAAACAGCUCAGUCUUGACCAUGGUUACCUCUACAGAGUAGGAAUCAAAGGUGUAGAGGCAUGAGGCAGGGAAAGUUUCCCUAAUGAGCUUCAUAGCACUUGCUGGCUUUUUAAACUGUUUACAUGUUUUCUUUCUUAAACAUUUUUUAAAGUUUCAUUACAGGAUAAUGCCACAGUAAAAUAUUUUCUGAACAAAAAAUUCAUUAAGAUGUUUGAAAAUCCAUCUUUAAACAUGCUCUUCAGUUUUUUUGAGGAUAGAAUGUUGACCAUUGUGAAAAAAUUAAUAAUUACUAUAUAAUGUUUUAUCCAUAAUAUAACUAAUGAUAUAUUUAAAUUAUAUGGUAGGAUUUUCUCAUUCACACUCAGGUUUUAAUUAACGCCAGUACCACAGAUGCACCUCACAUUUUUCUCUGCAGGUCAGAUCUGUCCUUUGAGCGCUAGACCCAUAUAUCACAACUCCCUGUAUGAUAUCUCUAUUUGGAUGUUUUACAGGUACCCUAGAUUCCACAGGUUCAGAAACAAACCUGUAAUCCUUCUCUUUGUUUGUGCUCUUUGAUUUUUCCCAUUGUUUCCUAAUUCAGAGACGAGACCACUAUCCAGUUGAGCAAAUCAGAAAUCAACUUUGACACCUCCUUCGCUUUUGCCCCAAUUUCUAAUUCAUCACCAAAUUUCUAUACAUUUUUACUUCCUAAAUAUCCCUUAAGGUCUUCCACUUCUCUCUACCUAGUCUCCAUUGCUAUCCACAGUACAGGCUAUUACCAUUUCCUGGCUGAACUACAGCAGUGGUUUUCUGACUGGUCUUCUCAUAUAUUCUUUUACCCUUUUUCCAUACAAUAGCCGUUUUUUAUACACACAUGAUUUCUUGAUCAUGUCACCUUUCCUACCUCUGAGCUUUAAAUCCUUCAUCGGCUUCCCAUUGUUCUUAAGAUAAAAUCCCCAAAUGUUAAUGGCCUAUAAGGCACUUCAUGAUUUGGGCCCUACCUAUUUUGCUUGAUCUUUGCUCUCUACAGUUUUUCCCAAUGUACCAUGCUCCCAUGCUCUGCUUUGGAAUGAUGUGAAAGAGAAAAACAGUGGCUGUGAUAGCCACAAGCGAGAUGGCAGGCAGCAGACCGAGUGCAGAAGACGCAGACAGAAGAUAAAAUAAUGAGCAAGUUAAAAUAGUUAUCUAAAUUAUAAACGUGUAUUUAUGUGCCUUUAACCUAGCAAUUUCUGUGAUCUGCAGGGCAAGGACAUUGACUCUAAUACUUGUACUAUCUCCAGCAUGGUAUCUCCUGCAUACUAGGCACUCAUUCAAUGUGUGGUUGGUAGAUAAAUAGAUGAUGAUAGUCCCAGUUUUAAAUACUCUUAUCUAGUUGCCUCAUAAAUGCCCAGAUUUUCAUAAGACCUAUAUAUCCAGUUGCAUUCUUUGUUUCUGUUUGUUUUUUUAAUCUGGAGACGUGGUCUCGUGUUAAACAGUUAGCUUUUGUAUACUCUUAUAGUCCUAGAAACAUCCACUAUGAUAAACUGCACUGAAUAUGAAGCAUAACUUGCAGUCUGAGUGAGCCAUUAACCAGUGCCUAGUACUCUUCACUGUAAUAGUUACUAAGAAAUCAAAAAUUGUUUACAUAAUCUUUAAGAAAGGAAAGAAUAUGGCACAUUUUAUAAACCGUUCCAAUAUGUCUACUUAUGUUUUGUAGUGCUGUAUAUACUCUGCUACUAUUUAGAAGGAAUUAACCCUCCUAGAUCAUUUUAGCUGGUGGAAGUUUAGAUGCCAGAACUUUAUACCUAUUGCUGCAAACAUUUCAUAAAGUAUGAUUUCUUUAUUCUUUUUCUCAGGAGAGGGUUUAUUUUGCAUCUUAACAUAGGAAAUGUGUCUCUGUUUAUUAUGAGAAAUAAUUUUACAGAGUAAAUUUAUAAGAUAUUUCUUGGUUUUUGUUUUGAAAUUAAGUAAAUACCAAUUGUUUCAGUAAUGUGUUUGGGUUGUCCUUACAAAUGACUUACUGCUCCACAAAGGCUACAUUUUCAAAUAGUUAUAUUGCUUUCACUCUUAAAGUUUACUUUUGCUGUUUGUAGUAUGUGGGUUGAUUGACAGUUUGGUUUUUUCCUCUUUCAGCACUUAUAUUAUGUCAUUUCACUGUCUUCUGAUGCCUCCAUUGUUUCUGAUGAGAAGUCAUCAUUUAAAUUAUUGUCAUUCUGUUUCUUUGGCUGUUUUCAAGAUUUUCUUUUUGGUUUUCAGGAGUUUGACUAUCUUGUGCCUAUGUGUAGUCUUUGUUUUUUUCUAUUCGGGAUUUGCUGAUAUUUUAAAUCUGUAAAUUUAUAUAUUUUACUAACAAAAUUUUUAGCCAUAAUUUCUUCAAAUUUUUUUUCUACCUCAUUCUUUCUCCCCUUUCCUUCUGAAUCUCCAAUUACAAGUAUGUUAUGAUACCUUGCCACAGGUCCCUAAGGUUCUGUUUCUCUCCUCCCCCUCGCCCACAGUCACUUUUUUAUUCAUCCUUCAGAUUGGAUAAUUUCUAUUGCUUUGUCUUCAAGUUCACUGACUGUCAUUUCCCAUCCAUGGUUAAGUCUACCCAGUGAAUUUUUUUCAGUUAUUUUAUUUUUUAGUUCUUAAAUUUUUAUUUGCUUUAUAUAUGUAUAAUUUCCAUUUCUUUGCUGAGAGUUCCAGGCAUAUUUGCACUUAAAUCCUUCAGCAUAGUUAAAAUAGAUGCUUUAAAAUACUUAUGUGCUAAUUCUAGCAGCUGGCUCAUCUUGGGCUUUGUGUCCAUUGGUUGCCUUUUCUCUUGAGUAUGGGUCAGUUUUUUUCUGUUUAUGUGUAACAAUUUUGGAUUUUAUUUAGAACAUUAUGAAUGCCAUGUAGAGACUCUGGAUUCUGUAUUCCUCCAGUGAGUAUUGAUGUUUGGUUUGUUAUCUGUUUCAAGCCAGAUAACUUGACUACACUUAAAGUAUAAGCUCUGAAAUCGCAGUUCAGUUAUUUUAACCUUAGCCUUGCUGCUUGAAUGGAAUCUGUCGCACAUAUGUAUAGUUUGGAGAUCAAAGAUAAAUACAGAGUUUAUACACAGAAUUUAGGGCCUCCUCUCUGUGGUUCUCUCCUUCCUGUGAUUUACUCACUAAGCUUUCAGCUGUUAUGAUCAUGCCAUUGUCUGUCCUUUGGUUCAUCAAGCAAGUAAGACUGCAGGUUUUUUAUCUGAGUGUUAGCUACCCAAACUAACUGGGACCUGCUCUCUGAGUAAAAGCCAUUAAAAAAUGGAAAGUUACCCUUGCUGUUUCCUUCUUCCAAGUGCUGACCCCUUUUUCUUCCCUCCACCAAUUUGUUUCUUCCUCCUUCAGGUAGUUUUUUAUGCAUUUCUACUGUUUAUAGUUGUUAUUCAUGAAAGAUUUGGUCUGGUAGGCGUUACUCAGCCAUCACAGGAAGUAGAACCCAUAAAAUAAAAUUGUACAAUUGAAGAAUGUUAUCAUUUGUGUAGGUGAUAGUCUUUAUUAGAAAAGCAGGCAAGUAUGGUGAGAGAUUUCAGUGUAUGUUUUAAUAAUGAAAUACGUUGAAAUUUGUUUUCAUGGUUCAUCCUCCUUUAAAUAAUAAAAAUGUCUCAAUCAGACUAUUUGCCUCUCCCUCAAAUUGUGUAUAAAUUUUUUUUUUUCAAAUCUAGAUCAUUUGAAAUAUGUUUUGGAAGCCUUAUAGAAGGAAACUAUAAAGAAACCUUAUAAUAAAAUAUUCAUUUUAUUCAACAAAUAUGUUGCAUCUUCUGUGAGCCAGGAAUGAUCCAGAUCCUGGAGAUAGAACAGUGAACUUCAGAGUCCUUGAUCCCAUGGGGCUAAUGUUUUGGGGAUGGAGAGAUAAUAAAAUAUAUCUCAGGUAUUGAUACAUGUUAUGAAAUAAAAGCAGUAUGAGGGUGCAAUGGUGGGAGAUGGGGAAGAGUUAUGGCAUUAUUUAGAUAGAGGGAUUGGUCAGGGAAACUGUCUCUGAAGAAGUGACAUUUGAUCAACAUUCUUAAUGACAUAAGAGAAGGGAGUUGCAGGUGGAUCUAAGGGAAAACUGUUCCAGUAGUAAAGGAGCAGCAAAUCCGAUAGCCCUAAGGGAAGAACAAGAGUGACUUCUUUGAGAAAUCACCAGACUGCCAUUUUGAAUUGAGGGAACAAGGAGAGGGUAGAAGAUGAAGUUAGAGGGGUGGUAGAUAGCCAGGGGCUUUGUUACAUUGCAUUUUGAACAGGGAAAGUGAUGACUCUGAUUUACUUUUCACAAAGAUCACGCCGCUCAGUAAAGAAAAUACUGGGGACGGGAAGAAGUGGUAUGUUGGCAAAAAGAAGGAAGGUGGGGAGACCUAUUGAGGCCUUUGCAGUAGUAGUCUAGAUGAAUUAUGAUGGUGGCUUGGACAAGAGCAGUAACAAGUGGGAAAAAUUGGUUAGAUUAAGAAUACUUUUUGUAUAUAAGCCAAGAAGUCUUGAUGGUAGAUUAGAUGUGGGAUGAGAGACCAACUGGAUGAAUGGUGGUACCAUUUACUGACAUGGAAAAGACUGGGAAAGGAUUGAUUUGGAUGGGGGAGGAAUUAAGAGUUUGAUUUUGGACAUACUGAGCUUGAAAUAAGUUGAUACACAAAAGGAGAUGUCAGUUAGCCAGUUGGAUAUGUUAGUCUCAAGGAAGAGAUUGGAGUUGGAGAUAAUAAUUUGCCAAGCACCAGUAUAUAGAUAUUAUUUAAAGCAAUAUAUUUGAAUGAAAUUACCUUGAAGAUGAAUGUAGAUAUAGUUGAAAGGAAACCAUAGAUCUGAACUCUACCAGCCACCAACAUUCAGAUGUCCAGAAAAGGAAAAGGAUCCAGCAAAGUAAACUGAGAAGAAUCUGCCAAAAAUGCUUGGACAGAAGAGAUGAGUACUAUUUCCACUAAGGCCUAGAAUUGCCUACUGUACAAAUAGUCCUGAUCAGGCAAUAUACGAAUGGCCCAAGGAAGCCACCAAAUUGAUUUUCAGGUUUUACAUGACCUGCGACAAAAAUUCCCUGAAGUACCUGAAGUUGUUGUAUCCAGGUGCAUGUUACAGAAUAAUAAUAACCUGGAUGCCUGCUGUGCUGUUCUCUCUCAGGAGAGUACAAGAUAUCUUUAUGGUGAAGGAGACUUGAAUUUUUCAGAUGAUUCUGGAAUUUCUGGUCUACGCAAUCACAUGACUUCUCUCAACUUGGACUUGCAAUCACAGAACAUUUACCACCAUGGAAGAGAAGGAAGUAGGAUGAAUGGAAGUAGGACUCUAACGCACAGCAUUAGUGAUGGACAACUUCAAGGUGGCCAGUCCAAUAGUGAACUAUUUCAGCAGGAGCCACAGACAGCACCAGCUCAAGUUCCUCAAGGCUUUAAUGUUUUUGGAAUGUCCAGUUCCUCUGGUGCUUCAAAUUCAGCACCACAUCUUGGAUUUCACUUAGGCAGCAAAGGAACAUCUAGCCUUUCUCAACAAACUCCCAGAUUUAAUCCCAUUAUGGUAACUUUAGCCCCAAAUAUCCAGACUGGUCGUAAUACUCCUACAUCUUUGCACAUACAUGGUGUACCUCCACCUGUACUUAACAGUCCACAGGGAAAUUCUAUCUAUAUUAGGCCUUACAUUACAACUCCUGGUGGUACAACUCGACAGACACAACAGCAUUCUGGCUGGGUAUCUCAGUUUAAUCCCAUGAACCCUCAGCAAGUUUAUCAGCCUUCACAGCCUGGUCCCUGGACUACUUGUCCUGCAUCUAAUCCUCUGUCACAUACCUCAUCUCAACAGCCAAAUCAGCAAGGCCACCAGACCUCUCAUGUCUACAUGCCAAUCAGUUCACCUACUACUUCACAACCACCAACCAUUCAUUCAUCUGGUAGCUCACAGUCUUCUGCCCAUAGCCAAUAUAACAUUCAGAAUAUUUCAACAGGACCUCGAAAAAACCAGAUUGAAAUCAAACUUGAACCCCCACAAAGAAAUAAUUCUUCAAAACUGCGUUCUUCUGGACCUCGAACCUCCAGCACUUCCUCUUCAGUCAAUAGCCAGACCUUAAACAGAAAUCAGCCCACUGUUUACAUAGCUGCCAGCCCCCCAAAUACGGAUGAGCUGAUGUCCCGUAGUCAACCUAAGGUCUAUAUUUCAGCGAAUGCUGCCACAGGAGAUGAACAGGUCAUGCGGAAUCAGCCCACACUCUUCAUAUCCACAAACUCUGGAGCAUCUGCUGCCUCCAGGAACAUGUCUGGGCAAGUGAGCAUGGGUCCUGCCUUUAUUCAUCACCAUCCUCCCAAAAGUCGAGCAAUAGGCAAUAACUCUGCAACCUCUCCUCGAGUGGUAGUCACUCAGCCCAAUACGAAAUACACUUUCAAAAUUACAGUCUCUCCCAAUAAGCCCCCUGCAGUUUCACCAGGGGUGGUGUCCCCUACCUUUGAACUUACAAAUCUUCUUAAUCAUCCUGAUCAUUAUGUAGAAACCGAGAAUAUUCAGCACCUCACGGACCCUACAUUAGCACAUGUGGAUAGAAUAAGUGAAACACGGAAACUGAGUAUGGGAUCUGAUGAUGCUGCCUACACACAAGCUCUUUUGGUACACCAGAAGGCCAGAAUGGAACGACUUCAAAGAGAACUUGAGAUUCAAAAGAAAAAGCUGGAUAAAUUAAAAUCUGAGGUUAAUGAAAUGGAAAAUAAUCUAACUCGAAGGCGCCUGAAAAGAUCAAAUUCUAUAUCCCAGAUACCUUCCCUUGAAGAAAUGCAGCAGCUGAGAAGUUGUAAUAGACAACUCCAGAUUGACAUUGACUGCUUAACCAAAGAAAUUGAUCUUUUUCAAGCCCGAGGACCACAUUUUAACCCCAGCGCUAUUCAUAACUUUUAUGACAAUAUUGGAUUUGUAGGUCCUGUGCCACCAAAACCCAAAGAUCAAAGGUCCAUCAUCAAAACACCAAAGACUCAAGACACAGAAGAUGAUGAGGGAGCUCAGUGGAAUUGUACCGCCUGUACUUUUUUGAACCAUCCAGCCUUAAUUCGCUGUGAACAGUGUGAGAUGCCAAGGCAUUUCUGAGCCAAAUGGCCCUGUAUCUUCUCUAAAACCACAUCUAAAGUUCAAGAAACUAGUCUGUCAUCGGGAAAAAGUUUCACUGCUACAUAGGAUUUUGUCAAAUUGAAGGUGUGACAAGAUGGUGUUCUGCUAAUGUUAAAUGUCAGCCCACAGAGCUAAUAAUACCUCAGUAUAAUGUCAUGAGCAGUUGAAAUUCAUCACAUGAAAAGUAAUCUGCUGAAAGACUUGGUUGCCCACUGCCUAACUGUGUACAGUGUUACCAGUGUCCCAUUAUGGAUAAUUCUCAAUAUGUUAACACCUAGGUGUUCCCAAUACCUUUUUCCCCUCAUGUCACUACUGAAUUUUGACAGGAGGAAGGAAUAGAAUGAUAGCUUGUUUUAUUUGUAAAGCUUUCAGUGAAACACUACAUACACGAAGAAAAGGAACAAGGUUUAACUAUUUAAGAACCAUUUGCUGCCGCAUAGUGCCAUUGGAUAGGGAAGAACUUCAGAAAUCUGUGGUACUCUUGGCCUUGUCUUUGUCUUCCCUGAACGUGUCUCCACUCUGUGAAGCCAGCAUCUAGGGGCUAAAGAUGCAAAGGAAAGCAGCAUGCAUUGUCUGUACAAAUGUGCAGCGAAAUACCCCAAAGCUUUUCCUACUGUACAGAUCUCUCGAGUCUGCUUUAAGUGAUUUCUUUUCUUCUUGAUUAUUUUCUUAUAUUUCUAUAUGUAUAGUGUAAUAGCCUUUUGUUAACUAAUUUUCUUUUUUCCUUUUAGUAAUUAAGCACGAUCAUGUCCCUUUUUAAGCCUUACCUGAGAGGAACAAUGCCUUAAAAUAAAAAAGCAUUAAUGAGAUGAAAGUAUGCACAGAAUAACUUUCCUCUACUUAUUCUGUACUUUGCCCUCAUGAGUUCCAAUGUUGUGUGAAGACAGGCAGAUGCUGCACAGUGAAUUGCAGAUGAUAUUACAGAAGUGAUGUCUGUAGGUCACAUUAAAUACUGACUUGAGCAGUGGGUGACACAACACAGUGUUUGUCUUCCACAGGGAAGCUUAAAACAAAAGAUAUUUUUAACCCACUGACAGAACAACAAGGUUAAGCUUCAUCUGCUUGGUGUCCCACAGAACUUGCACAAGCAGUUGUUAUUGGGAAAGUACAGUCUCAAAACCAGCAACAGCAGCAGUACCUACAGCCCUUUUUUUGGAGAGAAGUUUAAAUGCUUUACUGUUGGGGCAGUCCAUUUCUAAUCCUGACUUGGUGACAGUAUCAUGUGUAUUUAUAAAACAAGGCUAGCCAUAUUUAGGACAACUGAAGAAAAGCUGGAAAAAAAAACAAGCAAACUUGAACACUGAAGCAACCUCAAGCAUCUCUUUAUUUUGAUGAUAUAUUUUUGUAAGGAAAAUAUUCAGAUGAUCAGGAAUGUAUAUAACUGAAAUCAAGAAAAAGAACAGUAUGCAUUUAAAAAGACAGAAUUAUGAAAUUAUAUGAGUGCUUAGAAUGGGGCUAAGGGAAGUGCUGAAAUAGAGCAAAGGAUGGAAGAUAAUAUAGACUACCACCCACUGUAAAUGUUUGCAAGUGGCUGUGUUUUAAAUGGGAUUAUUACAGUUGAUCUCUAUGAAUGUCAGAGCCCUAACUUUCAGGCUUUGCAUUUUGUAUAUGGGAAGAAAUAUGACAAUCCUAGGUAAUUAAACCAUAGACCCAAAGCCCUUACGUUUGAUGCAAUUUAUUUUUAAAAUAGGCCUUGUUUUUCAGCUUCAUCUGCAGUUCUAUGUGAAGAUUGAUAAAUCAGUUUUUACUUGUUUUAUUAAUAAAACGUAAUUUGGAUAUCUUGAGUUGAUGGUUUUGUGAUUUAGCUGGGUAAACUAUCUUUGUAACAGAUAAGUUAUUUAUAAAAAUUAAAAAACUUAUAUUCUAA